CCUAGGCGUUUAGAGAAAAUGGCAGACGAUAUUGAUAUUGAAGCAAUGCUUGAGGCUCCUUACAAGAAGACUUGCCUAACGAUAUCUCACCUCUACUCCCAUGAAUUCACCUUUGAUUCCAGUGUGAACUGUCAAUCAUAAGGUAGUAAUUGAGUGACUUAUCGCUGUACCGUGGUCCCCUAGGUAAAAUGACUCAACUAAGAAUUACCACCUCCAGUUUGGUAUAGCAAAAAGGUGAAUGUAGUGGUUUGGGAAAAAGCAGGGGUCCAAGAAUAACAAAGCAUGACCAGUCUGUGGCAAGUUAAAUCUUCUAACAGUCUUAUAAGAAGAAAUGGGUGAGAUUUUAAAAUUUAUGUAUCUAUGUAAGACUGGUGAUAGUAAAUCUUAAAACAGUCCAGUGGCAAUCUGCUGCUCAGUUAAUAAUUACUAAAAUUCUUGGAUCCCUGAAUAGAAAUUAAAAAAAAAAAAUACAAGAGGCAGUAGAGUCAAUACAAGCUUAAUACAAGCUUAGAGUAAAUACAAGCUUAGAGUCACUUGAUGACUGUUUUACUGUUCUCCAUAUUGUUUUUAUUUUUAAUUAGGCCCUACCAUAGUAUUUCACACUAAAAACAAAGGAAUUAUAUUGGCUAAUAUAGUCUUUGACUCAUUUCGGUAUCUCAGUAAAAGUAAACUGUCUUUUCAUUGUUUCACCAGUUGGUGGUGAAAAUAGCAGUAUGCAUGCAUUAUCACUGGUGUCACAAACUGUAAGCUUUGUAAGUUAGCACUUUACUCCUAUAGCUGAUGUAAUCAAACUUUAAAAUAAACAUUUCACUAAACCUUUUAAAAAUAAUACAUUUGUUUUGGAUUGUAUAGCACGACCAUGUGGUACCAAUUUGGAUGAAUUCUUGAUAGAUUUAAAUAGUGUAUGUAAUUUUGUAAUGCUUAGACUCUUGAAGAGCUACUUUCUGUUUUAAUGUUAAGAUUCUUGUGUCUUAGUUUUUUUUAACAUGGAUGUAAUUCCAUGUAAACAGGUAUGGAAGUAGGAAAUGUUUAGGCUGGACUUGGUGGAUUAUUAAUUGACUUUCUUGGGUUCUUGGGAGUCAACAUUACUAAAGCAGUGUGAAUCCCUGUUUGCUUCAGGGCGAGAUGUGUGACAGAGGUGGCAUCAAGCUCUUACAGUCCCAACCCUCCAACGGAAAUGGGCGAAGAUCUCAGGAAUGGCAUCGGUCACAGGAAAUCGAUAGUGGCUGGCUGCUAGCAUGGCCACUUGGGGCUUAGGCAGAAAUAGAGCCAUGGUACUGACCAAAGGGACCAUAGCACAUGGAAUAAAACUCAAAACAGGACUUCAUGUUUUAUGGAAAUUAUAUUUAACCACUUCAACAUUGUAAAUCUGGAUAACUUUUAAUAUCUAAACUAUAUAAGAAAGUAAAAUUUAACAUGUUAAUAUGGAAAAUUUUUUUAUUUUUGUAUCUUGAUGACUUAAAUGUAAGCAACAAAGUGGUUAAACACAUACCCAUCUAAAUUUUUUUAUAGCCUUCCAUGUUAAACUAUAAGUAAAUAAUUAGUUUUAAAAUUGUUUUGUAUUUUCUUAUUCCUGUUCCCUUUACCCUUUGACAACUUGAAAUGUUACCACUUCGUCCUCAUGAUGUUCUUCUAUCAACCCUGCUUAGGAUGAGAACAAGUUGAGCAGUGCCAACGGCCAUGAAGAACGUAGCAAAAAGAGGAAAAAAAGCAAGAGCAGAAGUCGUAGUCAUGAACGAAAGAGAAGCAAAAGUAAGGAACGGAAGCGAAGUAGAGACAGAGAAAGGAAAAAGAGCAAAAGCCGUGAAAGAAAGCGAAGUAGAAGCAAAGAGAGGCGACGGAGCCGCUCAAGAAGUCGAGAUCGAAGAUUUAGAGGCCGCUACAGAAGUCCUUACUCCGGACCAAAAUUUAACAGUGCCAUCCGAGGAAAGAUUGGGUUGCCUCAUAGCAUCAAAUUAAGCAGACGACGUUCCCGAAGCAAAAGUCCAUUCAGAAAAGACAAGAGCCCUGUGAGAGAACCUAUUGAUAAUUUAACUCCUGAGGAAAGAGAUGCAAGGACAGUCUUCUGUAUGCAGCUGGCGGCAAGAAUUCGACCAAGGGAUUUGGAAGAGUUUUUCUCUACAGUAGGAAAGGUUCGAGAUGUGAGGAUGAUUUCUGACAGAAAUUCAAGACGUUCCAAAGGAAUUGCUUAUGUGGAGUUCGUCGAUGUUAGCUCAGUGCCUCUAGCAAUAGGAUUAACUGGCCAACGAGUUUUAGGCGUGCCAAUCAUAGUACAGGCAUCACAGGCAGAAAAAAACAGAGCUGCAGCAAUGGCAAACAAUUUACAAAAGGGAAGUGCUGGACCUAUGAGGCUUUAUGUGGGCUCAUUACACUUCAACAUAACUGAAGAUAUGCUUCGUGGGAUCUUUGAGCCUUUUGGAAGAAUUGAAAGUAUCCAGCUGAUGAUGGACAGUGAAACUGGUCGAUCCAAGGGAUAUGGAUUUAUUACAUUUUCUGACUCAGAAUGUGCCAAAAAGGCUUUGGAACAACUUAAUGGAUUUGAACUAGCAGGAAGACCAAUGAAAGUUGGUCAUGUUACUGAACGUACUGAUGCUUCGAGUGCUAGUUCAUUUUUGGACAGUGAUGAACUGGAAAGGACUGGAAUUGAUUUGGGAACAACUGGUCGUCUUCAGUUAAUGGCAAGACUUGCAGAGGGUACAGGUUUGCAGAUUCCGCCAGCAGCACAGCAAGCUCUACAGAUGAGUGGCUCUUUGGCAUUUGGUGCUGUGGCAGAAUUCUCUUUUGUUAUAGAUUUGCAAACAAGACUUUCCCAGCAGACUGAAGCUUCAGCUUUAGCUGCAGCUGCCUCUGUUCAGCCACUUGCAACACAAUGUUUCCAACUCUCUAACAUGUUUAACCCUCAAACAGAAGAAGAAGUUGGAUGGGAUACCGAGAUUAAGGAUGAUGUGAUUGAAGAAUGUAAUAAACAUGGAGGAGUUAUUCAUAUUUAUGUUGACAAAAAUUCAGCUCAGGGCAAUGUGUAUGUGAAGUGCCCAUCAAUUGCUGCAGCUAUUGCUGCUGUCAAUGCAUUGCAUGGCAGGUGGUUUGCUGGUAAAAUGAUAACAGCAGCAUAUGUACCUCUUCCAACUUACCACAACCUGUUUCCUGAUUCUAUGACAGCAACACAGCUACUGGUUCCAAGUAGACGAUGAAGGAAGAUAUAGUCCCUUAUGUAUAUAGCUUUUUUUCUUUCUUGAGAAUUCAUCUUGAGUUAUCUUUUAUUUAGAUAAAAAUAAAGAGGCAAGGAUCUACUGUCAUUUGUAUGCAAUUUCCUGUUACCUUGAAAAAAUAAAAAUGUUAACAGGAAUGCAGUGUGCUCAUUCUCCCUAAAUAGUAAAUCCCACUGUAUACAAAACUGUUCUCUUGUUCUGCCUUUUAAAAUGUUCAUGUAGAAAAUUAAUGAACUAUAGGAAUAGCUCUAGGAGAACAAAUGUGCUUUCUGUAAAAAGGCAGACCAGGGAUGUAAUGUUUUUAAUGUUUCAGAAGCCUAACUUUUUACACAGUGGUUACAUUUCACAUUUCACUAAUGUUGAUAUUUGGCUGAUGGUUGAGCAGUUUCUGAAAUACACAUUUAGUGUAUGGAAAUACAAGACAGCUAAAGGGCUGUUUGGUUAGCAUCUCAUCUUGCAUUCUGAUCAAUUGGCAAGAAAGGGAGAUUUCAAAAUUAUAUUUCUUGAUGGUAUCUUUUCAAUUAAUGUAUCUGUAAAAGUUUCUUUGUAAAUACUAUGUGUUCUGGUGUGUCUUAAAAUUCCAAACAAAAUGAUCCCUGCAUUUCCUGAAGAUGUUUAAACGUGAGAGUCUGGUAGGCAAAGCAGUCUGAGAAAGAAAUAGGAAAUGCAGAAAUAGGUUUUGUCUGGUUGCAUAUAAUCUUUGCUCUUUUUAAGCUCUGUGAGCUCUGAAAUAUAUUUUUGGGUUACUUCAGUGUGUUUGACAAGACAGCUUGAUAUUUCUAUCAAACAAAUGACUUUCAUAUUGCAACAAUCUUUGUAAGAACCACUCAAAUAAAAGUCUCUUAAAAAGGCCACAGGAGAUCUUCAUUUUUCAAAUGUUUUAAAGUUACAGAAAUUUGAGAACAGAAUUAGCUUCUUUUAGUCUCAAUUCAGUACUUGCCUCUUGGGAAAAUGUUCCGAGUCUGCGGAAACUUGCCCUCACGUUGUCCCCCAUGAAUUCCUUUAUUCUAUUAGAGUCUAGCCCUGUGUAUUUUAGAAGAAUGUAUCAAAACUGAGGGGUUUACCAAAAAGAAAAGGAAACAGCCUGGCCUUAAAACCUGGGCAUUCUUGGUCUCCUGCAUUGUCUGGGCAUAUUUAUGAAGAAAUUUUCACCAUUUACAAUACAUACUUAACAAAAUGGCUUAACUUCAAACUGGUUUCCAAAAUUGAUUUAUAUAUUAAUAUAUUAAAUAAGGUGCAUAUAUUACUGUAUUAAGGGGUUUUGAGCUUUCAUACUAGUUGGGAAGCAAGCUGUCACCAUUUAUACUCAAUUCUCUUCAACUGUUUAUCUCUUGGUAAAUCUUUUGAGUAGGAAAUGCUGCUCCUAGCUUAUCUUCAAAUACUGAGUUCCUUACCUCAUUUGUUCAACUUUUUUUUUUGUUAGCAUUGAAGCACAAGUUUUACAGGCUUAUUCAGAAUUUCAUAUCAGUCGUUUUGUUUGACAUUUAUCCCAAUAAUUGUUCUAGUGAUUUAAUUUGUAUGGAAACUCCCAAGGUUCAAUUUCUUUUUCUUUUUGAGAUGGAGUCUUGCUCUUUGGCCCAGGCUGGAGUGCAGUGAUGUGAUCUCAGCUCCAUCUCCCAGGUUCAAGCAAUUCUCCCACCUCAGUCUCCUGAAGAGCUGGGACAGGUGCGCACCACCGUGCCCAGCUAAUUUUUGUAUUUUUAGCAGAGACGGUGUUAGCCCGGCUGGUCUCACACUGACCUCAAGUGAUCUGUCCGCCUUGGCCUCCCAAAGUGCCGGGAUUACAGGCAUGAGCCACCGCGCCCAGCCUCAUUGAAAAUUUACUUUUCAAUACCAGACUGCAGAGUUCUUUGGGGCAGAGACACUCUGUCAGUGUGCUCUUUUUCCAAAGUAUCUCCUGCUAUCAGUUUUUCCCCUUGAACCAAGUCUUCCUAACAAAUUUGUUGUGUCAUUGCUUUCUAGGGAACUGGACCAGCAAAUGUGGCCUUUAGUGGUUAAUCUCAUCUGUGCCAAAAUUUAGUUGCUACCAGAGUGAAAUUUGGUGUGUAAAUAAUGUUCAGAGGAAAUGUGGUUGGAGUGUAGUAACUUGAAUAGUGUCGUGCAUAGAAAACAGCUCAUUCUGAGUGAAACUGUUUAUGUCCAAUCAGUUCCUGAGUCAGCAUCCCACUGGUUCGAAAAUCUGUAACUAAUCUGGUAAUGUCCUUAAUUUCCUCCUGCCUGUCAGUGUUCCAAAGUGUUCAUCUAGUUUUCUUUUAUCUUUAUAAUAAUUACUACCAUCUUUGAAAGUUCUGUUUAAGAAAUGCUUAAUGGGCAAUGCGGGUUAGUAACUCCAGGGUCUGCGUGGCCUGGGCAGGUGAGAUGGACAACUGCCUCAUUACAGAAGCUUUUUAUCAUCAAACUAGUAAGUUUUGUGGAGGGCAAGCUAUAUAGAUUGUUGAUGAGUGGUUAGAAAAUCAUCUGGAAUUUAGCCAGUUGAGAAGCUACAGAAGUUUCUAUUUUUUUUUACAGUGGAUGAACUGUUUUGCUUUUUCUGAUAAAGCCACUAGGUAUAUCUAAAUAACAACCUCGGGCUGGACGUGGUGCCUUAUGCCUGUAUAUGUGAACACUGGGAGGCGGAGGCGGGUGGAUCAUGAGGUCAAGAGUUUGAGACCAGCCUGGCCAACACAGUGAAACCCCGUCUCUACUAAGAAUACAAAUUUUUUUUGUUUUGAGACAGAGUCUCGCUCUGUCGCCCAGGCUGGAGUGCAAUGGCUCGAUCUCAGCUCACUGCAACCUCCACCUUCUGGGUUCAAGCGAUUCUCCUGCCUCAGCCUCCCGAGUAGCUGGGAAUACAGGCGCGUGUCAACACACCCGGCUUAAGUUUUUGUAUUUUUAGUAGAGACGGGGUGUCACCGUGUUACCCAAGAUGGUCUCCAUCUCCUGACCUUGUGAUCCACCAGCCUUUGCCUCCCAAAGUGCUGGGAUUACAGGCAUAAGCCACCGCGCCCAGCCUAACAAUACAAAAUUUAGCUAGGCAUGGUGGCACGUGCCUGUUAUCACAGCUACUCGGGAGGCUGAGGCAGGAGAAACGCUUGAACACAGGAGGCAGAAGUUGCGGUAAGCCGAGAUCGUGCCAC